GAUGAGACUGAAGCAAGGAUCGUUUCUGUGGUACCUCUAUCUGGACAAAAUAUACUGCUUAUUAUCCGUGAGAAACGUGAAGGCUUUGGCAGAAUAUUUUCAUAUUCUGGACGUGCACGGCAAGAACACCUUGAAUGAUGUGCUGUUCUAUCACUUCCUUCAUCAUGUGACUGACUUGAAAAAGGCACAGAUCAACAUUGUGUUUGACAUGCUGGACUGGAACGCUGUGGGCGAGAUCGACUUUGAGAAGUUCUACAUGCUGGUGUGCAUGCUGCUGGCCCACCAGAACCAUUUGGAAGGACAGUUUAUGUAUCGUCAUUCCCGGCCUGUCUUUGACCUGCUUGACCUGAAAGGGGAUCUGAGAAUUGGUGCAAAAAACUUCGAAAUGUACAGAUUUCUCUUCAAUAUUCAAAAACAGGAACUCAAAGAUCUCUUCCGUGACUUUGACAUUACAGGUGACAAUCGUCUUAAUUAUCAGGAAUUUAAGCUGUAUACAAUCAUCUACACUGACAAAUUACAGAAGAGGCAGAAAACAGAGGAGAAAGAAAAAGGAGAGAGAAAGAGAAGUCUCUACUCAAAAUGUCACAUCAAGUAGAUACAAGCUGAAAGAGUCUUGGAAAAAAAUGGGAUCUGAAAGUACAGAACAUGAACAUUGAUGAAGACUGUUAACAUGUCUAAAAAUAAAUUCAGAGCAUCAAAGUAGA